AGACACCGAGUCUCGCCUUCUGAGAUUGGCGGGUAACCUAGCAACGCAGGGACCGCGGCGGUAACUGUGGCUAGGGAAACCUGGAGCGGUCAGAGCAGAAUGCUGUCUGUAUGCCUGGCUGGUCCCCGCCUGACACAUGUGCCUGAGAUGCCUCCACACUUGGUCUUCCUGCCCUUGUGGCCCUAACACCCUCACAAAGCUGAAAACUGCUUCCAGUGAAAGGUUCUGUGUAAAAGCGACAGAGGACCUAAGAUGAACUCUUGAUGUCAACAGUUGUGGUUUCUGCAGCCACACUAACCACACAGAUGUCAGCACAGCUGCACUCACACCUACUUCUUCAUUUUGCAGGAUGGCCAGAGACAAUAAAAGCACGAGACCCAAGUAGUCUACCGAAGUCUCCAUCUCUGUGGACCUACAGAGGCACAGAGGGCUGCUCACAAGAUGGCUUUAGACAUUCUCGCCAUGGCCCCUUUGUAUCAGGCCCCUGCCAUCAACAGAAUAGGGCCAAAGACAGACCCAUCUAAAAGGCCAGCUGAUCCACUAAAACCCUUGGUUCUCUCUAGGACCAAACUCACCACCAUUGAGGCCAAAAGGAUCAUGUCCAUCCUGGAUGAGGCGAUCUACAAGGUGGAGCUGGUGACCUUGCUGUCGUAUGUGGCAUCCAACAGAGAGGAUAUGGAGGGGAUGCUGGGGGAGGACGUCAUGAGGGCAGUGAGAGAGCAUGAGGAUCUCUGCCAGGUCCUCCUUGAAAACGUCAGGUGCCUGAAAGAGAAAGAAAGGCAAUUGCAGGAGCAGAAAGAGGCUGAGGAGGAAGGGUGGCUCAGAGACCGCCUCCUUUCCAUAGAGCUGCAGAAAUCCAGCCUCUCACCACUUAUGCAGCAGAUCAAAGACUCCACCAAGAACGUCCUUAGACUCUUGCUCAGCAACCCCCAGGCUGCUAGGCUCCUGCAGAUGCAGACACAGGGUAGAAGUGCAGAAGCCCAGAAUUUUAUUGACAGCCUGAUAGAGCUCCGUGGUUUCCUGUUUGAAAAACUACUCACUAGUCCCAUGGAAGCGAGGGAUAAGGCCCAGUUCUUACAGGAUAUCAGUAGACAGAAUAGUAAUAACCAACAAAUCAUUGAUACUCUUGAAAAGGAAUUGGCGGAGAGAAUGAAGAACAGGAAUGCAGAGGUGGAAAAGGAGAACUUUGUGAUCCAAGAACUGAAAAACCACCUGCACCAGGUGCUCAAGUUCUCAGAGAACAGCCUCGUUCGCACUAAGCAGGAGGCUGAGAAGCAGCAGAAGGCCGAUUUCCGGGCAUCACAGGCCAGGGUGGCCAAGAUCCAGCAGGAGAUCCUGCAGCUGCAGUCACAGUUUUACAACCUGGUCAUGGAGAACCGGGAGGCAGAGCAGGCGCUGAGGAAGAAGAAAUAUAAAGUGGAAACGGAAAUCGAGAACUGGAUCCAGAAAUAUGAUACAGAGAUGGGUGAGAAGCAGGAGGAGUUGGAGGAUCUGGACGCUGUUCACAGGGAGGAGAAGAUCUCGCUGGAGGAGCUCAGGCGGAGGCACAAAGUGCUGGUGGGAGAGUUUGCGCAGAUCCGGGAAGAGCGGGAGAUCAACUCCAAGAAAAGGAUGGAGGCAGAGCAGGAGAUGGUGCGCAUGGUACGGGCGGCCACGCUCAUCCAGGCCCUAUGGAAGGGCUAUCUGGUGCGCUCCCUGCUCAGAUCCAAGAAGAAGCGGGGCAAGGGCAAAGCAAAGGACAAGGAGAAGGGCAAGCAGAAAGGCAAGGAGAAGGGCAAGGGCAAGAAAUGAGCUCUCCACCCAGCCCGCUCCUGACCCUUAUCUUCCCAGAGACCAGGCCAGGAAGGCCCGAGAUGGAGAGCACUAAAUUCACGGCUUUCAUGUUUUUAUUUAAUAAAUUAAAAAGUAUUUGAAGCCACA